AGAUUCGCUGCUCCGCAGCACGGCCGGAGCUGGUCGGGUCAAGAGUCGGGAUUUGUGGGGAGAGGUUUUCCACUGGUCAAGAGAAGGCUUUAAGAAAGACGGUAUUAAUCUCCCGUUGCGGCUCCCGCCUGGUCCCAUCUUCUGCCCGCUCCUCCAGGAAAUGAAUCUGCUGCCGAAUAUUGAGAGUCCAGUGACUCGGCAGGAGAAGAUGGCGACCGUGUGGGAUGAGGCCGAGCAAGAUGGAAUUGGGGAGGAGGUGCUCAAGAUGUCCACGGAGGAGAUCAUCCAGCGCACACGGCUGCUGGACAGUGAGAUCAAGAUCAUGAAGAGUGAAGUGUUGAGAGUCACCCAUGAGCUCCAAGCCAUGAAGGACAAGAUAAAAGAGAACAGUGAGAAAAUCAAAGUGAACAAGACCCUGCCGUACCUUGUCUCCAACGUCAUCGAGCUCCUGGAUGUUGAUCCUAAUGACCAAGAGGAGGAUGGUGCCAAUAUUGACCUGGACUCCCAGAGGAAGGGCAAGUGUGCUGUGAUCAAAACCUCUACACGACAGACGUACUUCCUUCCUGUGAUUGGGUUGGUGGAUGCUGAAAAGCUAAAGCCAGGAGACCUGGUGGGUGUGAACAAAGACUCCUAUCUGAUCCUGGAGACGCUGCCCACAGAGUAUGACUCGCGGGUGAAGGCCAUGGAGGUAGACGAGAGGCCCACGGAGCAAUACAGUGACAUUGGGGGUUUGGACAAGCAGAUCCAGGAGCUGGUGGAGGCCAUUGUCUUGCCAAUGAACCACAAGGAGAAGUUUGAGAACUUGGGGAUCCAACCUCCAAAAGGGGUGCUGAUGUAUGGGCCCCCAGGGACGGGGAAGACCCUCCUGGCCCGGGCCUGUGCCGCACAGACUAAGGCCACCUUCCUAAAGCUGGCUGGCCCCCAGCUGGUGCAGAUGUUCAUUGGAGAUGGUGCCAAGCUAGUCCGGGAUGCCUUUGCCCUGGCCAAGGAGAAAGCGCCCUCUAUCAUCUUCAUUGAUGAGUUGGAUGCCAUCGGCACCAAGCGCUUUGACAGUGAGAAGGCUGGGGACCGGGAGGUGCAGAGGACAAUGCUGGAGCUUCUGAACCAGCUGGAUGGCUUCCAGCCCAACACCCAAGUUAAGGUAAUUGCAGCCACAAACAGGGUGGACAUCCUGGACCCCGCCCUCCUCCGCUCGGGCCGCCUUGACCGCAAGAUAGAGUUCCCGAUGCCCAAUGAGGAGGCCCGGGCCAGAAUCAUGCAGAUCCACUCCCGAAAGAUGAAUGUCAGUCCUGACGUGAACUACGAGGAGCUGGCCCGCUGCACAGAUGACUUCAAUGGGGCCCAGUGCAAGGCUGUGUGUGUGGAGGCGGGCAUGAUCGCACUGCGCAGGGGUGCCACGGAGCUCACCCACGAGGACUACAUGGAAGGCAUCCUGGAGGUGCAGGCCAAGAAGAAAGCCAACCUACAAUACUACGCCUAGGGCACACAGGCCAGCCCCAGUCUCACGGCUGAAGUGCGCAAUAAAAGAUGGUUUAGGGUC